AGAACUUGACCCUGUCAACUUGAAAUAAUCGAAAGAAUUAGAACCUAGCUUGAAAGAAGUUAUUUAAGCUUUGAAAAGCUGAGAAUAUCCAUCUGGGAAACACAGACUCCAGAGAAAUGAGGGACUGAUGACACCUGGAAGAAAUAAGUUGCAGAGAUGCAGAAUGCAAUCAUAGAACUAGAUGCAUUUGGGGAAUAAGAAAGCAUUAGAACGAUAGAGCUGGAACAAAUGCCGGCUUAUCCCCAGUCAUUUAAGAAAGUGGGAAAGGUGAUUUACAUGGGACCACAGCACAUCUAGAUGAACAUCCUGAGUGAAAAGAAACUGACAUAAAGAACACAAAAUAGUGACACCAGAGAAACGAGUACCGAGGGUGUAGACCUAUAUAAAACACUGGGGAUUAAAGAGUGCACAGAAGCCUCACAUCUCUUCUGCUGCAUAAGGUAAAGAUACGUGUAACAAUUCAAAAUUAUUUUGGGCAUACUAACAAGGAGUCAUUUCCAAUUCUGUAUUAAUUACGAACAUGCGAUGUAGAUCAUAGAUGUGCUGAACUAGUAACAGUCAGUCAGUAGAUUAUAGUCGUUCUUUUGUAGAUUGCUUUUCAAUGCACAGCUGUCUUUGGGACAGCCGGCUAUGGACGUGUGUCUGAGCUCCGCGCAGCAGCCUGGGCGCCGGGGGGAAGGACUCAGCUCCCCGGGUGGCUGGUUAGAGGCUGAGAAGAAGGGGGCUCCGCAGAAAGACAGCACCGGGGGAGUCCUAGAAGAAUCCAACAAGAUAGAACCAUCUCUUCAUAGCCUCCAGAAAUUUGUUCCUACAGAUUACGCCAGCUACACUCAGGAGCAUUAUCGGUUUGCAGGAAAGGAGAUUGUCAUCCAGGAAUCCAUAGAGAGUUACGGAGCGGUGGUGUGGCCAGGGGCUAUGGCUUUGUGUCAAUACUUGGAGGAACAUGCCGAGGAAUUGAAUUUCCAAGAUGCAAAAAUACUUGAAAUUGGUGCCGGACCAGGCCUUGUUUCCAUUGUGGCCAGUAUUUUAGGAGCUCAAGUCACAGCAACAGAUUUGCCUGAUGUCCUGGGAAACCUUCAAUACAAUCUUUUAAAAAACACACUACAAUGUACAGCACAUCUGCCUGAAGUGAAAGAACUGGUAUGGGGGGAAGACCUGGACAAAAACUUUCCCAAGUCAGCUUUUUACUAUGAUUACGUCCUAGCCUCAGAUGUGGUCUACCAUCACUACUUCCUGGACAAGCUGCUCACCACCAUGGUGUACCUUUCCCAGCCAGGGACGGUGCUGCUUUGGGCAAACAAAUUCAGGUUCAGCACCGACUAUGAAUUUUUAGAUAAAUUCAAGCAAGUUUUUGACACAACACUGUUGGCUGAAUAUCCAGAGUCAUCAGUCAAACUUUUUAAGGGGAUACUAAAAUGGGACUAAAUCCAACAAAAUGCCUUUCACAACGUUACUGUGUCUUUUGAGCAAUGUGUUAGAAAUUGCUUUGGUAAUAGACUUCUUUCACAGGAUUGAGAAGGUAGUGCAUAGAAACAACUUGUAUACUUGGAACAAAUGUAACAAUACUGCAGAAACUUUCUAAUUUCUAAGAUAAUUUAAGAUUAUCUGGUUAAUCUAAAUAUCUAAAAAGAACAACAUAAAAACAUGAAAGUAGCUUUGUUGGUUCCAACGAAGUUACAUGUUUAAUAAAUCUUACAUGGAUAAAGUAA